GCCCCGCCCUGCCCGGAGCAGCUCGGCAGAUGCUCUGUGCUGCGGCCCGGAGGUGAAGGGCUGGAUGCACAGUGGGAGCCGGAGGCGGGGGGCUGCAGGGAGCACACCAGCGACCGGCCCUCCAACCCUCCAGCCACUCAGCAACAUCGCCACAGCAACCAGCAACCAGACGGCAGCAGCCGAGGCAAACACAAGCGGACGGCUUCCCACCGUCGCCGAGGACAGGGAAUGACUACGGCAAAUCAGGCCACUUUGCCAACUAGGGAGGUGGAGUGUCACUAGUGGGGAGGGGCGGCCACCGCCCGCUGCACAGAGCGCCAUGCCGGCUGGAGAAGAGGCGCUGGGGCAGGGGCUGCAGUGUGGCUCGGCCUCACCCCCCUGCUGGCACUGAGUGCCUCCAGGGCAGCUGGGCUCUUGUCUGCCUGGUCUCAGUGUCCCCUGUGGCAAGAGGGAGAGGUGCCCCAUCCCGUGCUCCUUGUCUGGGCCCGCUGCUGCCAGACCAUGGGAUGUCGGCAAAGCUCAGAGGAAAAAGAAGCAGCCCGGCGGUCCCGGAGAAUUGACCGCCACCUGCGCUCAGAGAGCCAGCGGCAACGCCGCGAAAUCAAGCUGCUCCUGCUGGGCACCAGCAACUCAGGCAAGAGCACCAUCGUCAAACAGAUGAAGAUCAUCCACAGCGGCGGCUUCAACCUGGAGGCCUGCAAGGAGUACAAGCCCCUCAUCAUCUACAAUGCCAUCGACUCGCUGACCCGCAUCAUCCGGGCCCUGGCCGCCCUCAGGAUCGACUUCCACAACCCCGACCGCGCCUACGACGCUGUGCAGCUCUUUGCGCUGACGGGCCCCGCUGAGAGCAAGGGCGAGAUCACACCCGAGCUGCUGGGUGUCAUGCGACGGCUCUGGGCCGACCCAGGGGCACAGGCCUGCUUCAGCCGCUCCAGCGAGUACCACCUGGAGGACAACGCGGCCUACUACCUGAACGACCUGGAGCGCAUCGCCGCAGCUGACUAUAUCCCCACUGUCGAGGACAUCCUGCGCUCCCGGGACAUGACCACGGGCAUUGUGGAGAACAAGUUCACCUUCAAGGAGCUCACCUUCAAGAUGGUGGACGUGGGGGGGCAGAGGUCAGAGCGCAAAAAGUGGAUCCACUGCUUCGAGGGCGUCACAGCCAUCAUCUUCUGUGUGGAGCUCAGCGGCUACGACCUGAAACUCUACGAGGAUAACCAGACAGCCUGGGGAAGUGGUUGUUCACCAGAAAAGGAAAUUCUUGAUGAGAAACCCAAGCGAGGCUGGAAAUUCACUGGAUUCCAAAUGAUUCUGACCUUUCAUGCUCUACCAGUAAUAUCUGGAGAUGGAAAACAAACAGGCUGCAGAGGAAAGACAAUCCCCUCCCGCGAUUCCUCCCGCAGGCUGGGCUGGCCCCGGAGGUGAGCUGGCCCCCAGAGUGGUGCCGGCAGUGAGGACAGCCCGUCUCCAGCCGGGCCAGGGCCAGAGCCAGUGCUGGCACGGGCUGGCACAGGGCUGCCACUCUGCUCUCUCCUUUUGGAACGUGCUGAACUGUCCUCCCUGGGCCCUGUCAAAGGCAAGGCAGCCAAGAACAGGCCAUGCUCGUUUUCACAAAAGCCGAAUGAACCUUGGGGCCCAGUGCCAGGGCUCUGGACACGGCUCCUCCAUAGCCCUCCUUCCGUGCUCAGCUUCCAAGGCCUCAUCUUCCCUGAUGCUGGCAGUGCCUCCCCACCCCCACGCCUGGCGAAGGAGCCACAGCCCCCCGGCCCACCCGCUGGCUUCUGCGUCAGCACGUUGCCAAGGAGAACGUCAGUGUCUCUGGGCUCCCGGGUGUGAGGGCUGCAGUGAGUGCAGGGCAGCACCUCAGAGCAGGGAAGGCAGAUUUCCGGGUGUCUGUGGAGCAUGGCAGCGAGCCACAUGGGGAGCCACGCCCCUCCAUGGCCACGGUUCCCACCCUCGUCCGAAGGAAUUGGCAGUCCCUUGCCCUGACUAGGGCCAAGUCCUGCAGGUGUGUCAGGCACCCCAGUGCCCCCAAGCCCAACACCCAGCUGGGGCUUCCUCAGGCAGCACAGGAGGCCUGAACACAGCCCAGCAACACAAGGGGGUUUUUCUGGCGCACCUGUCCCCUGAAUGAUCCUGUGGGGCAGCAGCGCCUGUUAUUUUUGUCACAGAUCGAGGCACUGAGGCUCAGGCACACAGCUGGCGCUGGCGGGCCCCCAGCCCUCAAGUCCACAAGGACAGCUCCUGAGAGGCCAUGUGUCACAGGACCCACCACGGGCCUCCCACUUAGCCAGAGCCAUGGCAGAGGCUCUGCCCCUCGUCUUUAGUACAUUCACACAAGGGUCAGUCAGCAAAGACAGUCACUCUGCUGCCCUAGGAGGGAAAGGCAAAGUGGAGAAGCUGGCACCUACCAGCCCACACUGAGGGACAGACACAGGUGGCUGUGACCAGCAGAGCCUGGGUCUUCACUCGGCCCCACUGGAGGCACCUGAGGGGGUAGGUGGGCACUUGUUGCCCAACCUCUGCCCUUGCGGAUCAGCUAAUGGACUCUGCUGGCCACCAAAUGGUGUGGGAUCCUUCAGAAGGCAAGAUUAAAAGGUCUAGUUGUAAAGCAUCAAAUGUUCUCAUGUGGAAACCCACAGGGAGCUCACUGCCCAUUUCCCGACGGAGCUGUCAGCAUUCCCAGCCCUGUGGCGGGUCUGUUUUGCACCUGUGAUGGACCUGCUGUGCAGGCUCAAGGCUCAGGCUGGGGCCAAGUAUGAGGGUGAGCACAACUCUCCCAGCAGCACAGGGAACUGGGGGACAAGGAGGAGGCAGUCACACCAGCCCAGCUACAGCUUCAUUUCCACAAAGCCUCUGCUACCAGGGAUACCUGCCCUGUCUUUCUAGAGCUGGCAGGCAGCAGUUCCCAGCAGUGUCCCCAUUGUGCUUUCAUCUAGGACCCACAGUAGUCACUUGGGCCCCACAGGCAGGCUGGGUCACAGCAGGGUUCACCGUGGGAGGCCUGGUGUCUCUGCCACUUAUCUGAGAGACAGCUGGUCAACAUGUUAUCAGUGAGGGUAUCCAGGGGACGGGGGACAUAAGAACAUGCCUUUUGUGGGGCAAGUUCUGCAGGUGGCAAGUGCUUGAGCAGCCAGCCUCCAGGCAGGUGGUCUAUGCCUGGCCCUGGAUAGUGGUCCCUUGUCCUGGGGCCAUUGGCUUCCUGAGGAACCCCUCCCCACUCCAGGGCAGGUCAGCAGCCUCAGCACACCACGAGGGCAGGUCCACACCCACCCGGCACAGCCUGUGCUCUGAGCAGAGGGCCUGGCACACAGUGGGUGCUCUGCAGACUUUGUGGAGCGGGCGGGAGGCGGUAGGCUUGGGAAGAGCUGGAGCUCCAGAGCCCUGGCUUCUGGGUGCAGAGCAGCUGGGACACUCAGCCCUUCCCAAGGAGACCCUAUGGGUGCUCGUCCAUAACAGGAGUGUAUGCAGUACCCUGAGGAGGGGCUGCCCAAGGCCGUCCUGUGAACACAGCGUGUUCCUGCCACCCUAGCGCUGUGGUUUAUCAUUUAGCCCAAAAAGGGUGCUUGUUUUAGUGCUUUUAAAAUGGAGUUUAAACAUUUGUGCCAUAAAAUGGCGUGUUGUGGGUGAAACAAGGUGUUUCCAGUAAGACAGGCUUAUACCUAUUGAUGACAGAGCUGGUUAUAUUUGCCCAAGGAGGGAAUUACAAAUGGGCAAUAGCCAGACACAGAUGAUACCCUCUCCCCAGCAUACCAGGGCUUAGAUUGAGAAGGGACCUUAUAUAUCCUUUAGUGUUCCUAACCAGCCGGCUUUGCAGAUGAGGAAACUGAGCCUCAGAGAGGUUCCUUCACAUACCGCAGGGCUGAGACUCUGGCUCUCAGGGAGGGUCCUGGCACUGGCCCCUGGGAAUUCCAGUGGCCCCCCUCUUCACCAUACUGGUCCCACAUCCUGUGGGUGCUGGGGUUCUCCAGCAAGGGCCUUGGGGGUAUAGACUGGGUUCCACCCUUGGAGCUGCUGUGUAGCCAGCCUUCCCUCAGGAGAGUGGAGGACAGUGACACCUGGGCUUGGGAGAGGUGAGUGGCUGUGAAGGUUGACACUCCCCUCGUCCCCUUGUCUCCUGGCCUAGUCAGUGGCAGGACCACAGGGAGCCCUAGCAGAACAUGGCCUCACUCUGCCUCCUGUUCCUGACCUGGUCAAGGGCAUAGCUCCAAGCCAGAAGGCCUGCCGCCCUUUUCCCGACACACACAGGUCUCCCAAGCAGUUCCUUCUGAUCUUGCAAUGUGCCAGGGCCACAUGCAGUUUGUCUGCAGCAUCCUCAAGUUAUCAUGACCCUGGAACAGCAGAGCCUCCUGACCAGAUCCAGAGGCAGGGCCAGGCUGGCACACUGGGCUCCCAAGGACUGGACAGCCCCCAUGGCAGUGCAGCUUGAGAGGCUCCACAGGGGUGGGAGACACAGAGGACCAAGCCCACAGCAGCACCCUGAUGGCACCUCGCAUGGCAGGCAUGGAAUUGGGAGCAGGGCUCAGCUGGCCACAUGAUAUCCCCAGCCCGCAUCCCUCUCUAAGCUUGGCCUGGCUUCCUCUCUAUGGCCUGUUAUCCUACCCGAGCACUGGAGCGAUGGGGCCAGCCUCAAGAGGGCUGGGCACACACCUAUAGCUGGGCCACCCGUGGCCUAGAGGCCCCACCAACACUUGUGAACAGCCCCUGCCAUCCCUUCAGCACCGGCUCCCCGCAUCCAAGUUCCCUUGCCUCAUUGCCCAGGACUCAGCCUUAACUGGGGCUGCGGCCACCUCAGUGGGCCUUCAGCCGCUCUGAGCCUGUGGCCAGUGCUCAGUGAAUGAUGGGUAUCUGCUCGCCUAGGGUCCCAGGCUUUAUGCGUGACCCCAUGGGAUGCUGGCUCAAGCCCAAGAUGGGAGGGGGAUGAGCAGGGAGGGGUGGAGAAGGCAGCAUGUCCUGGCACCUAUUUGAGGCCCUUGCUAGCACUUCAGUCCUUGGGUUAGCUCCUUCCUUCCUCUGCUCCCAGGGAGGAUGCAGCCACAAGGCCCCUGUCAAAAGCAGCUGCUCCUUUCCUGUCACACUGGGAGCUUCCAAGGGUGGGGCCAUUUCUUAGCCCGCCUUGUGCAGUGGCUCCUUGCCCUGGGUAGGUCCUUGGUCAGAGGUCAGCCACAAGGCAAGAGGCGGCAGGGCCCUGGGCUCAAGCCCUGCUGCUUGGGCUGCCCCCACACCUGCUCUGCCUGCAGGGCCUUUUCCUUUGGCCCCCAACUCCUCAUCAUCAUGAACCUGGUGGCUCUGUCGUUCAGUGCAUCAGCCACCCCUCCAUGAUGGUCACCUCCUGCUGUGUCACUAGAGGCCAUUCCCAGGGCACAAGCUGUCACUGAACACAGCAGUGCAGCAGCCAGGAGGCCAACCCCAUCACUCUGUCUCUUCCACCAUGAUGACGUUGUCAGGUGCCUUGGCAGAACCUCCAUGGGGAUGCCCAUGGUGUUCCUCAGAUCUCUCAGACAAGUGUUCCUGCCACAACAGGAGGUCAGCCAGCGUGGGCUCUGCUGGGGCCUCCUUUAUGGGAAGGCAGGAGUCAGUCUCUUGCCCUAGUGCUGGUAAGCCUUGAGGGAGGAGGGAGGAGAGAACAAGAGAGUUCUCUUCGGCACCAUGCCAGGCAGGGCUGCUUCCUGCAGAGGAGAGUGCUGAGACCCAGGGCUAGUGGUGGCAGAGCCUCCCUCUCUGCAUGCCAGGGCAGUGAGGGGCUAGAGCUGGCUCAUACUGGCUCACAAGAGCUAAUUUUUCAAUUUUCAGGAUGUUUGUGAGCUGUUUGACAUUAUAUUUGUGGCUUCAAAGCAGCCAGGUAGGAGUAAUCACACCCCAGGAACUGGCAAAUACUACAAAACAGUUCUACUCCUCCCCAGCCCCCGCCUCCAUGCCAGUUGUUAGACCUUUACCAGUGCACCACAGCCAGUGACUCCCAAGCAUGGCGGGGAGAGUCUGCCAGCCAGGCUCAGUCACUGGUGUAUGGCAGGAUUGAUCCGCUACUGCCAUCUUACUGAAGAACCCGACAGUGUCCUUGCCUGUCAGUCUCCCACUGUGCUUCCCCAGUGACUCCCAGCUCUGACCCUGUGGCCGCGUGGGUUGCAUCUGUUCGUGUUUACCCCGCUGGAGAAAGGGAAUUUGCCAGAGCGGCUCUUCACUUGCCUGCCUCCCUCCCGCUCUUCCUCGGCAGAUUUAAGAGAAUCCUACUCCACAGAGAGCAACCUUGCAUUGGCUAACACGAGACCACAAGCUGGGGGCCAUCUGAUGUUCUCCAUCUGAGAACAAGCCCUGUGGCAUCCUUGCAGGAAGCAGUCCUUGUUCACCCAGUAUGUGUGGGCCCUGGGCCUGACAAACUCAGUCUAGGGACAGAGGCAGUCCUAUCCCUUCCUCCCUCAGGUCAGCUGGGGAUGGCAUCAAGCAGGCCCUGGAGGACCUGUGUAGCCAGGGCUGGCCUCAGGCUGGCUUCCCCAGUGCCUACAAAUGCUGGCCGCAUGCUCUCUGUGACUGGCCCUGAGCCUGCCCUAGGAAACAGUUUUCUAGGUGCAGAGAAGCCAGGAACAGGUGCCUCCUCUGUCCCAAAGACCAACAUUUGCAGGAGAGACGGGGGCCUAGACGUUGGGAGCAGGCCUGCACAGAUUGGGAUGAACGUGGGGGUGGUGAUCUGAUCUGGACCUUGCAGAAUCCAGUCAAGGCUGUGGGGGAGCAGUGGGGACAGUCAACAAAGGCAGGACUGAGGGGGCUGUCGGGGGCCAUGGAGAGCACAGAGCUAUGCACAGUGCCCUGCAGCGGGAUGACGGAGGACCAGGCGGUGUAAGGUCUAAGCAGGCAGGGCAAGGUCGCAGGCACAGUGUCCAGUCCCCAGUGUGGCCCAGGGUGGGUGUCGCUGCCUGAGCGCCCUGUGAUGACGGAGCCAGGGUUCAGCCCCAGGACUGUGUCCCUCCCAGUUUAUACACCUCCUGCUCUGCCUCGUGAUCAGGCUGGAUGCUCACAAUGAUACCCUGUCUGAACUGUUCCAAGAGCUUCAGGGCAGAGCUGCUUCCCACCCCACAUCCCCUCAACCUGCAUCGGCUAGGCUUGCCCAGGCCAGUGGGUAAUUAAUUUCCUGAGCGCAUUAGCUCUGCUCAGUACACACACAUGAGAACAGCUCUGGGUUUUAAGACACAGAUUACUAUUGUUUUAAGGGAUUUGUAUAAUCCAGUAACUGAAAAACAAUUUUCCACUAUCUAGAACAGACUCCAAGGUGGAGGCUAAGAGUGCUGGGGGCCUUGCUGACUUGGGGAUCCCUAGUAACCAGUGUAGAUGGGGGGAUCUGCCACUCAGGGGAGUCCUGUGACUGGCCAUGAACAAGACAAGCAGUGAGGACAGGAUGCAGCAGCAAGGCUCUGUGCUGACCGGAUGCAUAGCCCUCUUCACCUGAGGCCCCACUGGCUCAGUCUAGUUUCUGGAGGGAUUGGAAUGACAGUCAGCUAGGGUGCAUGGCCCUGGGCAUCUCAGGGGGGACACCCAGUGUUGGCCAGGGCAGAGUGAAAGGUGUUUCUUCUCUCUGCAUGUGGCUCCCGUCUGGAUAGUGGACAAGCUUAGGCCAGCCCAGGAGCCUGGCUGCAGCUCACCCUAAUCCCUGCUUCAUCACACCUCGUGGUGGACAUGUCCUCAGCUCAGGUACUUUCUCUAAUUUCAUUAAUAAUGAAACCAGAGUCGACUGGGGGCCCUGGGCCUUGUAUCCUAAGGUUCCCAGCCCAGGCCGGCCACGGCCACAGCCCCACACACCUUUUCCUGGCCUGUGGUGACCAGGGGAGAAGCACAGCAGCAUCCUGACCAAGGGGGCCCAGAGCCUCGAAGGCAACUUGGCUCAGCUGGAGGAGUGACUAUGGGCAAGGUCCUGCCCCACAGGGCCACCCAGCUCAAGCAGUAACAACCCAAAUAUGUUUUUUUAAAGGAUGAAUAUUUUUGAAAACCAUCUUUUUGGCCAUAGGCAGAGGUUCCCCACUGGGAUCUCUCCCCACUACCCCCAGUUUCUCAUGUCCCUCCCAGGAAAGAGCCUGAGCCUGCUGCAGAGGGGUUCACAAGCCCUUGAGCCUACAGGUGUGGGUCCGAGGCUGCAGUGCCAGCGGCUAGGAGUGCAGAGUGCACCCACCUUGCUGAACAAAGCAAAGGCAAACCAGGCAAGGGUGUCGGCCUUGGGUUCCUGGGGAUCCUCUGGAGCUGAAACUAGGAGGGGUUUCUCACACUGUGCUUUCUUCGCAUGGUGAUGGCGUGCAAGCUCCUGGCCAGGCCUGUGUCUGUGUUGACAGCUUCCAAUCUACAACACACCUGUAUCAUGCUGUUUGUUAAUUUCCCUUCAGCGACUGACACUGGCUGGUGGGGAGCAGGGGUGCAGGUUACUUAAAAGCAGCAAGAUUUAACACAAAAACAAAUAGGAGACAGUUCUCAGCUGAAACAGAAGUGGACUGGGGCUUUGGAAGAGGCCAGUCCUCCCAGUUGGGCAGGAGAGCUUAUGGGGUCAAGGUGAGAGCAGGUGGGACCCAGGUGCUGAGGGUGCCCACGGCCUCCCUUUCUGGGUCUGGGUGUGAAGCCAGGGAGCAGGACACAGGAGCUCCAGGCCCUUUCGGAGCAAAUGCUCCCACCAUCUUGGAAUUUUCUGUCCCAGGACUGGGAGUCUUUGAGCAUUGUUAAGGCACCACCUCCAGUCACGUGACUCCCGCCACAUAUCACACUUACCCUGGGGCUCUGCCUCCUCAGCAACUUUGACCAACACCCUUGGGAAUACAGAGGCUCCCAUUUGGACCUAAGACCCUGCAAGUCAGUGAUGGUUGAGAUCUGGUGAGAGCAAAAAAGCAAAACAGAGUGACAUGAGGGUAAGGGGGGUGGCGCCUUGGGCCUGUGCUGGAGAACAGCAGCCACCCACCUGCAGGGCUGGACAGGGGUGCCAACAUCCUGGAGGCUGCACACAGACUUCUGGGAGAGCUCUGCCCAGUGGGUGAAGCCCAGCUGAGGCAUGAGAAAGUGCUCUGUGUACAGCACCGUCUCCAUCUCACACUGGGCCCUGGCACUGUGGGUGGGGCCCUGGCCUGGCUGUGGCCCAGGGUAGUCAUGUGGACUUGUGUCCAUCUGGACUGCCCAGGUGAAGACUGGCCCAGCAGCACAGUUCCUGAGCUCCUGCCCCUCCCCUGGCUAGUGAGGAGGUAGGGCAGUUCUGGAAGUACUCUGAAGGCUCAGGCUGUAGGAUAACAUGUGUGUGCUGGCUGACAACAGAAUAGUGGAAAUGGAAGGCCCAGAGACGUGAGCGGUUGGCAGAGCCUGGCGCAGGGCAUGCUGGUGCACUGCAUGCACAACCUCUAAGCCUCCCAGCCCGAAGGGGCUCCCCACCACACAGAUGAGGAAACUCGGGUUUCAGGAAAAGUUGUCCCUGUGGCAAAGUGGGGGCCUUCUGACCUGGACAUCCCGCUGCUGCCCAGGGGAAUGGGCAGGGCUGGGAAGCAGCCACCCUUGCCAUUACUACGGGUCACCCCACCCCCUCCACACUGCACACACAGGGAAACCAGGGAGGGCAGACAGGACUGCCCAGGCAAGGUGGCAAAGCCGAACUGCUGCGGAAGGCAGGGAGCAGCACGCUCAGCUGUUUCUGGCAGGUUCAGAGCAAGGGCUUUUCAGGCCAUUAGGGCCUGAGCUAGGGCUUUAGCGGCAGCCUGUUAUCUUGUUUAAACAGCCCUUGCUGUUUGAGGUGCCAGGCUUAGCUGGUGCUGUUACUAUGAGCACUACAGUUGUCACCAGGCAUAGUUGCAGGGGGGAGGGGGCCACCGGCAAGCAGAGGCUCUGACUUCUGGACUCGGCUGGAACACACCCCUGCCCUGGCCCCCAUCCCAGAGGAGCCCCAUCUGUCGCUGGCCUGGGACCUACAGGCCUGAGUACUCUGUAAAAUGGGCCCCUCCCAAGCUGCCUGUGCCCUCCUGAGCUGCCUACAUGGGCAGCUGAGCAGCCCUGUGCGGGUGGGCAGGAGCGGUGGCCUUUCUUAUCCCCAGGGAAAAGUCGAGGGCCUCAUGAAAACCCAGGGCCUGAGAGUGUCUGAGGACAGGAGUUGUGGCCACCCCAGGUUGUCAAUCCUCCUGUGCCACUCGAGAGUCUCCACUUCAGCCAGGCAAGUCCUGUGAACUGGGGGCCUCUGUCUGCAGGUGGCAGCAGCUGGGGUGUAGGGAGCAGAAGCUGGGGCGGGAGCAGGGGUCCCAAGCACAGUGUUCCAGCAAGAAGCACCGGAACCCACCAAGGGAGCGCAGCAGUGGAGUCGGGUCCUGGGCCUCUGCACACAGAACCCCAGGGGGUUGGCCGCAGGGUGUGAAAAUCAAACCCACAUUUUCAUUCACCAGAAUACGGGAUCAGAUAGUUCCUGAUCGUUUUAAAGCCGGAAGAGCACCUGCUUAUCAAAUGCCUCUUCAGUCUGUUCUGCCAGAUUGACCCAUUGACCGACGAAGCCACAGUGAGGAAGGACACAGACCAGCUGUCACUGGAGGGCCAGCCCAGGGCAAGGCCUGCUGCGGGGGAGGAAGGCCCAGCCCGAGUCCCUUCAAAGCCUCCUAUAGGUGCCCAUCACCCACCCCAGCCACACCCUAGGCAUCCACAGAAGUGGCGGGUCUGGGUGUGAGGCCUGUGCCCCCCGCCCUGAUCCAGCCCAUCUGUGGGCCAGGAGCAGGUGCAUCUGUGCAGAAGGGUGGGGCCAGGGGCACACAGGUGGGGAGCAGCCAGGCAAUCCCAACCCCUGCCCCUGUACACAGCUGCCACACCAAACGCCUGCAGCAUGUGCCAUCUGGCCUUGCCUGCCAUCCACCCCGUGCUGGGCAGAGCAGGGGAGAGCGGUCCCCAAGCAGACAGCACUGCUCAUAGGCAGGCCAUGGGCAAUGAGAACAGGGGCCAAUGGUGCUAAAAGCUGUGCAGCAAAUUAAAAGGGUUGGGGUUGUGACUAGGGCUUACUUCAAGUGAAGGAGUCUGAUAGCUGACCAGCUACACAAACCCAAAAGAGCAGCCCAUGCAGGGUAGCACAGCAAAGGCCUCGAGGUGACAGAGACGGAAGCAGGAGUCAGGAGACAGCCGGGAGAGGCCUGGAUUACACAGCCUGCCAUGGAAGGCACUGGAGGGUUUGCACAGGGGGCAACCCCAGAGCAGAAGCAGGUAGAUGGAUCCUGAGGAGACAUGACCAUGGUAGAAUGGGAAGGAGAUUGUCCAGGAGGUGCCCUCAUGGGGCAGAACUCAGAGCCAUAGCCCAAAACUGGACCCUGCAUGCAAUGUCCCAGGGCCCCAGCUUCCUGCCUCAUAAGCUGUGUCAUGGCCUAGGACCUUUCUUCCCAGGCAGGAGUCAGCUCCACCUGCUCUCUGGCUGGCACAGCCUGGUGCUGGCCACCCCAAGUGUUAGCAUCCUCUGCCUGCUGGAGAGGUGGUGUCCCUAUUUGGGGACUCAGUACUCUGAAGUCAGGGUUUUGCCAUGCUCUUCUCUGUCCUUCGAGGCAGGAGACAUGCUGUGCAUGCUACAGGAGCUUAGGAAUUGUCUGAGGGUGACCAGUGGGGGUCCAGAGGAAAGGUGCUAGGAAGACAUGGAGGCUUCCAGGGGAGGCUGGGCCUGAAGCUCAGCUCCAUAUCCGAUGUGUCAUCGUGGGAAGAGCAGUGUCUUCAUGAGGCCUGGACAGUGCCUGGGUGGGAGAUAGCUCCAGCCUCCUUGGAAGACCUAUUGACCACGUUUCUCUUGUGACGCACUUCACUGUCACCCAGAAUAACUGCUGUCUCACAGCUACCAGGACCCGAGCCUCUGGGGUAAGGUAGAGUUCAAGGAGAACCAAGGCAGCCCAAGUGAGCCUGGCAGCAGAGCCGAGGGCAGCCCCACCAAAGCCACGGAGCCAGCCCUGCUGGCAUCCAGAGGCCAGGGUGGGCCUGCCCUCCCAUGGCCCCGAGCUCUGCCCCCACCCUUUAGGAUUGCACCCUGCCUUGUUAAGGGAUCAGCUGCUGCUCCUCUCAGGUCUUUUUGGGAGUCCUGAAUCUGAAGUGAGCCUGGGAGAAAGGGAGUCAGACAGGAGAGGGGUGGGUGCUGAGCCAAGUGAGGGUCUCAAGACCAAGGGGACCCCAGAGCAUGGGUACCCAGGGCCUACACUUGGGAGGCCUGUGGCUGGGCCAGGAGGAUGAACCAGUGUGGAGUUGAGAGCCAUGGAGUGGCAGAGAAUGGGUGCCAGGAGCUGAGGUGUUCAAGCUGGAACAGAGCCCUCCGUGCAGGCAGGGCCGAGCCUGUCUCCCUCAGCAUCUCAGAUGCUCACAGAACCACGGGGGCAGCAGGGUUCAGUGUUAAAGGCCAGGCUAGAGGAAUGGAAACAGCUGCCCCAGCCCUGGAAGCUGUGGGAGUGGUGGUUGCCCUGCAAGAGAAGGCUCAGAGCAUAGGCAGGCCUUCUGCUGGGAGGCAGGACCCAGCAGUUGAGCAGGUACCAGCCCCCCACCUCUCAGUUCCUGAGGCUGGCCGUCAGCACCAUGUGCCCUGUGCUGUCCCCGCAGACUGGCUCCAGGGACAGACAGGAGCUCACUGAGUCAUUAACCCUCAAUCCAAUUCUCCAAUCUGUCAAGGUAGCAUUGAGGUUUGCGGGAGGAAGAGGGAAGCACUAACCAGAUUGGACUGUAAGUGACCCUGGUCAUCCAGCUCUGUCCCCAGACACCUCCCCAUUUCCUGAGGCUAGUAGCAGUGGGAGGAUGACCAGGCCUGAGGGGUGGUUCGGGCUGUCUGGUGCUUUCCUUGGGGCAAGGGUAGUGGGCCAGGCAAAGGGGCCUAGGCAAGCCAGGUAACCCCUCUGAGCACCACUUUCCACAUCUAGAAUGGAAAUGUUUUGAGCCUCGUGAGCCCAGGAGCCUCUCACAGUCACUUCUCGGAGGUGAACAGAACUGGAGGGCAUCACGGCAGCCCCCACACAAGAGGAAGUCCAGACUGACGAGGCCACAGGGUGACAAGAGCGAGCCACGUUCUGGGGCCCUCCCACCAGGAGGCCCACCCCACCCAUGGUGCUCCAGCCAGGAACAGGUCACCAGAGGUCCUCCCCUCUCCCCUGCCCACUGCCCUGUCUCUCAGGGCACAGCAAGGCAGGUCCUUAAAGAGACAGAGGGAGAGCAGGGUACCCUCGCUACCAGAGACCCUCUCCCACCACCUGAGCAGAUGGGCAGUAGACAGUGUUUGGCCAACCAGGCUGUGUGCCCCUGUGGGCACCUGCCCCAGCUCAAGGGUCAGCAGCUUCACCUGCCACUGGUCUGCUGUGGUGUGAGACUCUGAGGGUGAGGGUGUCCACCCUGGUUGUCAUAGAAACAGCAGUGCGUCUGCAGAGAGUUCAUGCCAAGCUCAGCAGAGGGAGGAAGCAGCUGGCCUGGGAGGCAGCUGUUGUCAUUGACUCCUGAGAGCUCAGUGUUGGGAAGGACCCAAGGGCCCACCACACUCUGAGGCUGGCGAGCACACGGGGCAACUCAGGCCUCCCUGCCCACCAUCUUUCUUUGGGCAGCUGCACCAUGUUGUCUGUCCUCUUGUCCACUUGGGGUCAGCGACGAUUCCAUCUAGGUGCUGGGUGAACCAAGCACAGGGGUGCUGCCUCAGAGCCACUUCGAAUGAGGGGGUAGGAUAGCACUGGGAUUCCAGCAGGCGAUCAUCAUUUGCUGGGGGGCCUGCGCGCCUUCCCUGUGAGCGUGAGCAGGAAUGACUCAUGCCUCCUCCACCUGCUCUCACACUGAGCCUCUGCCGGGGAGUGGCCUCACUGUCUGCCUGGUUUUUGUCUGUCUGCCCCUUUGUCUCCCAGUCCCAUUACCUGUCAUGCAUCCUAAGCUCCUGAGGACAGAGAAGGUGGAGAGUAGCAGAGCCAGAGAGGCUCUCCUGUGACGUGGCUGGCUCUGUACCGAGCAGGGGGUGCGGCCACAAAUCUCCAAGCCCAGGCCAGGGGAGAGAGGCAAGCGCACUGGACUCGGUUCCGCCUAGUGGCAAAGAGGCCCAGAAAAGUCUCAAGUGCUUGGGACAGGGCCCCAUCUGCAUGUGAUGUGUUGGGGCCUCUGGAAACGGAGAUGCCAAGGCAGUCUUCUCUGAGGUCAGUGGUGAUGCCAGAGAGGUGAGGCUCAGGCCAUUGCCAGCUGCACCAGAGACACCAAAGCACUCCAGGGUCCCCCAAGGUCACUUUAGUAGAACCCAGUGACCAUCUUGGACAAACAGCUUAUUUUACUGAGGCAGGAGCUGCGGCCCAGAGCAGAAGUGACAUGCCCAGGGUCUCACUGCAGUUUGGUGGGAGAAUUAGGUUUCAGAACACAAGACAGCCAGUACCUCCCAGGCCCCUUCCUCAGGGAGCCAGCAGGGUCGUGGGCAAGCGGCCAGGCUCCACAGGGCAAGCCCCUUUGGACUUAACCCUGUUUGUGACAGCCCUGGUCCCUGACAGUCCUCAGAUCCCGGUGGCAGUGGGCAGUGGGCUGUCUGAAACCAAGGUGCUCCUUAUUUCCAAACCAGAGGUGUCUGAUCACAGAGUGUGUCACUAGGAGCAUGUUCUGAGAAGCCAGGGAGCCUGGUGCCCAGGUUCCCAUCCUUAGACCAGUCCUCUGUCCCUUGCAGCCUUAGUCUCAUCCACAGCAAGACUGGAGCCUUGGGGGUAACCAGGAAAGGACAGGCACUGCCCCUGGCAUUCAUGCAGGGACCAGGAGGGCCAGAACACAGGCACCCUCAGCCUCCUGUCUUCACCCCGCAGCCCAAAGGAGGGCUGCCUGACCUCCGGGCCUCACUUCUCUCCCAGCACCAAGAAAGAGGUUCCCAGCUGCAUUUCUGGUUUCUGAGGGGCCCUUCUGCUUCCCCAGCUGCCACAGCCCCAGGCCCUGCCUGGGGGUCUCUGGAGGAAGCAGAAGAGGCAUCCUUCGGCCCCGCCCCAAGCACACCAGGCUCUAGGGCCCAGUGCUCACCAGGCCGUUUGCUCUUUGCCUCCCAAGACCGUGGGAGGUCCAGGGACCUGGUCAGUGGCAAUGCCUUCCACCAGGUACAUGGUUGAAGAGGUGCGGGGAGCAUGCCAGGGUGCAGCCAGGAGGCCAGAUGACCACAACCAGGGGUAUGACAGCCCUGGACACAGCAGGUCUGUGGCCACGGCAGGAGGGCGAGAUGGACACUUAGCAGGAGGCUGGGCUGAGCUCCUGGUGGAGUCAGGGUGGGACUGUGGCAGGGAGACCCCCUUCUCCAGCAAGGACAGGGCCACUUCCUGAGAAAUGGAGCAUCGGACAAACACCAGCGGGGUGGGAAUGGCAAGUGCUCAAGGUAAGCACGAUGCAGCUGCGACCUGUAGACUGGCUGCAAUGGGGAGCCUGGCCAGGAGAAGCCAGAGACGGACACCAAGGUCAGAUCCUGAAGCACAGAAGACCCUCAGUGGGGAUAGGGACCUGGCUGCAGGGAGCAAGGUGGCCAGUGUGGACCCAUCAGGAAGGCAGGGGCCUGGUCUGGGGACCCCACAGCUCCAGCUGGGCAGAGCUACCCCAUGCUGUGCUGUGCCAUGGAAUACCAGCCAAGAGACCAGGAGCAGGGAGCGUUCUGAUAGGAACAUCCAGCUUUCAGGUCUGACGUGGCCCAUUUUACCAGAAGAAGGGGACCUGCUCUGAGCAUAGCAGCCCCCUCUGCCUGGAACCUCACAGGGCUCACCUCCAGGCUAGCACCCUGCCCCUGCGGCUGACCCUGGCCAGGAAGACACAUGUUAGACAGCUGGCUGGACUUGGUGCCUGCUGUGGCUGCAACUCCCCUGGGAAGACAGCUGAGUGUUCUGACGUUGGCUAAACUGCAUCUUUACAACAGCUGGGGCCCCAGCGCCACCUGGCCCUGUGCCCAGGCAAGGCCCUGCUGGUCCCAGCAUCCUUCUCUCCCACAGAUCUUACCCCGGCUCCCACCCCAGCACUCUGGCCAGCACCGCCUCCCUGUUUCAUAGUCCCAUCAACCCCUCACACACUGGCUCCCAGCUGCUGCCACCACCUUGAGCUGUCUCGGAUAGCCUCCUGCCCAUACCCCUUUGGCCUGAGGGUAGAUGUAGGCCAAGAGCUUGCACCUACAAGCUUCCCCAAAAGGGAAGUGAACUCAGGAAUUCCUGAUGAGGAUUCCAGGACUGGCUGGGGAAGCACGGGGUUGCAAGCGAAUAAGCUAUUUCCUUUGCGACUGAUACCAUCCUUGGAGUGGAUUUCCUCUGGUGCCUUCCCUGUUCCACAGCUGCAGAGGCAUCUAGCACAGGGGGCCAACACCACAGGCCCCUCCACUCGGUACACCUGCCAGGACCUCGGCGCAUCAUCAGAUGGUGGGGCCCACUCGCCCUCUCCCCACUAGAGAAGUCUGGGAAUGCCUGUGUCCCAGACCCCCUCGGCAGCACUCAGGAUGGCCCAGGCAGGUUGCAGAGGCUCCUGCCCACCAGGCCUGUCACACAGAGCUCUGGGAAAUGGAGAUGGGCAGUCAGUGCCAGCCAAGGGCAGGCACCCGCUACCGAUGGAGGCAUGUUGGUCACUGUGUCAGCAGUGCCCCAUGUCCCUCCAGCCACACCCUGCCCAGCAGACAGGCAGCCCCACCAAGGUGUCCCCAAGCUUCCACCACAAAGGGAGGCCCAGAGGGGUGAGAGGCUUGGCCGGUACUUUGUGAAAGGUGACAGCAUGAAGCUCAUCUCUGUAUGAAACCUCUGCCUCGGCCCCUCAGUCAGGGUGCUGCCCUCAGAGCCUGGUACUCGGUGGCCCUGGUCAGGCCUGGUGGCUCAGCUGCAGGCUGGGUGGCCGCAGGGCUGGCCUGUCCAUGGUGAAUGGAGCGCAUUCAUGUCUACAACCCCGCCCCACAGCUCUGCUCUCGGCGUGAAAAAGCUGAAUUCACGGUUCGGAUGAACACUCCCAGCUUUUCUACAGUGGGCUGACUUGAGCUUCUCAGUCUGUAACAGAACUGAGGACUUGCUCUACAGAUGAGGAAACUGAGGCCCAGGGUGGGACAGACCGGCCCCGGCCCCACCCUUCCCAGCAAUGCGGCUGCAUCCCCAUGCCUCUGUGCCUCUGCCAGCCCCUCCUGCAAUGCCUUCCCUUCCCCUCAGCCCCCAGAGGUCCAGUCAAAACGUCCUGCUCUUGUAUUACCCCUCGCCCCCUGCAUUCCUGUGGUGUGUCACCUGUCAGAGUUGUAGCUGGCCAGCACUAUCUGCAGCAGUGCCAGCUGCUCACAGUCACUUGUGCCUGGGUGUGGGGACUAAGCUGUCCAUGUGUAUCCCACAUCAGCCCUCAGCCCCCUCACGAGGGAAGUAUGCUUACA